GCUCCUUUUUCUGCUCCCCAAGUGAGCCGGGCGCGCGAGAGGCAGGCGGGGCGGCGCGGAGCGGAGCAGGCAGCCCCGCGCGCUCGCCCACCGCCCGCUCCGCGCAGCUCCCCGCGGCCGCUCUCGUCGCCGCCGCAGCGGGCGCGUCGGAGGGAGCCCAGCAUGGCCGGGCCGGGCUCGCCGCGCCGCGCGUCCCGGGGGGCCUCGGCGCUUCUCGCUGCCGCGCUUCUCUACGCCGCGCUGGGGGACGUGGUGCGCUCGGAGCAGCAGAUACCGCUCUCCGUGGUGAAGCUCUGGGCCUCGGCUUUUGGUGGGGAGAUAAAAUCCAUUGCUGCUAAGUACUCCGGUUCCCAGCUUCUGCAAAAGAAAUACAAAGAGUAUGAGAAAGACGUUGCCAUAGAAGAAAUUGAUGGCCUCCAACUGGUAAAGAAGCUGGCAAAGAACAUGGAAGAGAUGUUUCACAAGAAGUCUGAGGCCGUCAGGCGUCUGGUGGAGGCUGCAGAAGAAGCACACCUGAAACAUGAAUUUGAUGCAGACUUACAGUAUGAAUACUUCAAUGCUGUGCUGAUAAAUGAAAGGGACAAAGACGGGAAUUUUUUGGAGCUGGGAAAGGAAUUCAUCUUAGCCCCAAAUGACCAUUUUAAUAAUUUGCCUGUGAACAUCAGUCUAAGUGACGUCCAAGUACCAACGAACAUGUACAACAAAGACCCUGCAAUUGUCAAUGGGGUUUAUUGGUCUGAAUCUCUAAACAAAGUUUUUGUAGAUAACUUUGACCGUGACCCAUCUCUCAUAUGGCAGUACUUUGGAAGUGCAAAGGGCUUUUUUAGGCAGUAUCCGGGGAUUAAAUGGGAACCAGAUGAGAAUGGAGUCAUUGCCUUCGACUGCAGGAACCGAAAAUGGUACAUCCAGGCAGCAACUUCUCCGAAAGACGUGGUCAUUUUAGUUGACGUCAGUGGCAGCAUGAAAGGACUCCGUCUGACUAUCGCGAAGCAAACAGUCUCAUCCAUUUUGGAUACACUUGGGGAUGAUGACUUCUUCAACAUAAUUGCUUAUAAUGAGGAGCUUCACUAUGUGGAACCUUGCCUGAAUGGAACUUUGGUGCAAGCCGACAGGACAAACAAAGAGCACUUCAGGGAGCAUCUGGACAAACUUUUCGCCAAAGGAAUUGGAAUGUUGGAUAUAGCUCUGAAUGAGGCCUUCAACAUUCUGAGUGAUUUCAACCACACGGGACAAGGAAGUAUCUGCAGUCAGGCCAUCAUGCUCAUAACUGAUGGGGCGGUGGACACCUAUGAUACAAUCUUUGCAAAAUACAAUUGGCCAGAUCGAAAGGUUCGCAUCUUCACAUACCUCAUUGGACGAGAGGCUGCGUUUGCAGACAAUCUAAAGUGGAUGGCCUGUGCCAACAAAGGAUUUUUUACCCAGAUCUCCACCUUGGCUGAUGUGCAGGAGAAUGUCAUGGAAUACCUUCACGUGCUUAGCCGGCCCAAAGUCAUCGACCAGGAGCAUGAUGUGGUGUGGACCGAAGCUUACAUUGACAGCACUCUCCCUCAGGCACAAAAGCUGACUGAUGAUCAGGGCCCCGUCCUGAUGACCACUGUAGCCAUGCCUGUGUUUAGUAAGCAGAACGAAACCAGAUCGAAGGGCAUUCUUCUGGGAGUGGUUGGCACAGAUGUCCCAGUGAAAGAACUUCUGAAGACCAUCCCCAAAUACAAGUUAGGGAUUCACGGUUAUGCCUUUGCAAUCACAAAUAAUGGAUAUAUCCUGACGCAUCCGGAACUCAGGCUGCUGUACGAAGAAGGAAAAAAGCGAAGGAAACCUAACUAUAGUAGCGUUGACCUCUCUGAGGUGGAGUGGGAAGACCGAGAUGACGUGUUGAGAAAUGCUAUGGUGAAUCGAAAGACGGGGAAGUUUUCCAUGGAGGUGAAGAAGACAGUGGACAAAGGGAAACGGGUUUUGGUGAUGACAAAUGACUACUAUUAUACAGACAUCAAGGGUACUCCUUUCAGUUUAGGUGUGGCGCUUUCCAGAGGUCAUGGGAAAUAUUUCUUCCGAGGGAAUGUAACCAUCGAAGAAGGCCUGCAUGACUUAGAACAUCCCGAUGUGUCCUUGGCAGAUGAAUGGUCCUACUGCAACACUGACCUACACCCUGAGCACCGCCAUCUGUCUCAGUUAGAAGCGAUUAAGCUCUACCUAAAAGGCAAAGAACCUCUGCUCCAGUGUGAUAAAGAAUUGAUCCAAGAAGUCCUUUUUGACGCGGUGGUGAGUGCCCCCAUUGAAGCGUAUUGGACCAGCCUGGCCCUCAACAAAUCUGAAAAUUCUGACAAGGGCGUGGAGGUUGCCUUCCUCGGCACUCGCACGGGCCUCUCCAGAAUCAACCUGUUUGUCGGGGCUGAGCAGCUCACCAAUCAGGACUUCCUGAAAGCUGGCGACAAGGAGAACAUUUUUAACGCAGACCAUUUCCCUCUCUGGUACCGAAGAGCCGCUGAGCAGAUUCCAGGGAGCUUCGUCUACUCGAUCCCAUUCAGCACUGGACCAGUCAAUAAAAGCAAUGUGGUGACAGCAAGUACAUCCAUCCAGCUCCUGGAUGAACGGAAAUCUCCUGUGGUGGCAGCUGUAGGCAUUCAGAUGAAACUUGAAUUUUUCCAAAGGAAGUUCUGGACUGCCAGCAGACAGUGUGCUUCCCUGGAUGGCAAAUGCUCCAUCAGCUGUGAUGAUGAGACUGUGAAUUGUUACCUCAUAGACAAUAAUGGAUUUAUUUUGGUGUCUGAAGACUACACACAGACUGGAGACUUUUUUGGUGAGAUCGAGGGAGCUGUGAUGAACAAAUUGCUAACAAUGGGCUCCUUUAAAAGAAUUACCCUUUAUGACUACCAAGCCAUGUGUAGAGCCAACAAGGAAAGCAGCGAUGGCGCCCAUGGCCUCCUGGAUCCUUAUAAUGCCUUCCUCUCUGCAGUAAAAUGGAUCAUGACAGAACUUGUCUUGUUCCUGGUGGAAUUUAACCUCUGCAGUUGGUGGCACUCCGAUAUGACAGCUAAAGCCCAGAAAUUGAAACAGACCCUGGAGCCUUGUGAUACUGAAUAUCCAGCAUUCGUCUCUGAGCGCACCAUCAAGGAGACUACAGGGAAUAUUGCUUGUGAAGACUGCUCCAAGUCCUUUGUCAUCCAGCAAAUCCCAAGCAGCAACCUGUUCAUGGUGGUGGUGGACAGCAGCUGCCUCUGUGAAUCUGUGGCCCCCAUCACCAUGGCACCCAUUGAAAUCAGGUAUAAUGAAUCCCUUAAGUGUGAACGUCUAAAGGCCCAGAAGAUCAGAAGGCGCCCAGAAUCUUGUCAUGGCUUCCAUCCUGAGGAGAAUGCAAGGGAGUGUGGGGGUGCGCCGAGUCUCCAAGCCCAGACAGUCCUCCUUCUGCUCCCUCUGCUUUUGAUGCUCUUCUCAAGGUGACACUGACUGAGAUGUUCUCUUACUGACUGAGAUGUUCUCUUGGCAUGCUAAAUCAUGGAUAAACUGUGAACCAAAAUAUGGUGCAACAUACGAGACAUGAAUAUAGUCCAACCAUCAGCAUCUCAUCAUGAUUUUAAACUGUGCGUGAUAUAAACUCUUAAAGAUAUGUUGACAAAAAGUUAUCUAUCAUCUUUUUACUUUGCCAGUCAUGCAAAUGUGAGUUUGCCACAUGAUAAUCACCCUUCAUCAGAAAUGGGACCGCAAGUGGUAGGCAGUGUCCCUUCUGCUUGAAACCUAUUGAAACCAAUUUAAAACUGUGUACUUUUUAAAUAAAGUAUAUUAAAAUCAUAA